ACCAGACCCCUCUGAGGAUGGAGCAGGAGCUGGCUGCCCUGAGGCUGCAAAACUUCUUCCCUCGUGGAGACAGGGAGGCACCUCAGACACUCACCCCGGACUCCCUUGAACAGGGACAGGGAGGAACCCCAGGCAGCUAGACCCCAGCAGCAGCCACACGAGCACACUGUGGGGCAGGGAGGGGCAUCUCUUGAGAACAAAAGAUCCAUUUCUCGACUUUCCAAACUGGAGAGCUUCUUGAGAGAAAAGAGAGAGACAGGUACAGGUCCACGCCACCCACACACAGCCCUGUGCACACAGACCGGACACAGGCGUCCACAGUUCUGGGAAGUCAUCAGUGAUGAGCAUGGCAUCGACCCCAGCGGCAACUACGUGGGCGACUCGGACUUGCAGCUGGAGCGGAUCAGCGUCUACUACAACGAGGCCUCUUCUCACAAGUACGUGCCUCGAGCCAUUCUGGUGGACCUGGAACCCGGAACCAUGGACAGUGUCCGCUCAGGGGCCUUUGGACAUCUCUUCAGGCCUGACAAUUUCAUCUUUGGUCAGAGUGGGGCCGGCAACAACUGGGCCAAGGGUCACUACACGGAGGGGGCGGAGCUGGUGGAUUCGGUCCUGGAUGUGGUGCGGAAGGAGUGUGAAAACUGCGACUGCCUGCAGGGCUUCCAGCUGACCCACUCGCUGGGGGGCGGCACGGGCUCCGGCAUGGGCACGUUGCUCAUCAGCAAGGUGCGUGAGGAGUAUCCCGACCGCAUCAUGAACACCUUCAGCGUCGUGCCCUCACCCAAGGUGUCAGACACGGUGGUGGAGCCCUACAACGCCACGCUGUCCAUCCACCAGCUGGUGGAGAACACGGAUGAGACCUACUGCAUCGACAACGAGGCGCUCUACGACAUCUGCUUCCGCACCCUCAAGCUGGCCACGCCCACCUACGGGGACCUCAACCACCUGGUAUCGGCCACCAUGAGCGGAGUCACCACCUCCUUGCGCUUCCCGGGCCAGCUCAACGCUGACCUGCGCAAGCUGGCCGUCAACAUGGUGCCCUUCCCGCGCCUGCACUUCUUCAUGCCCGGCUUCGCCCCCCUCACAGCCCGGGGCAGCCAGCAGUACCGGGCCCUGACCGUGCCCGAGCUCACCCAGCAGAUGUUCGAUGCCAAGAACAUGAUGGCCGCCUGCGACCCGCGCCACGGCCGCUACCUGACGGUGGCCACCGUGUUCCGGGGCCGCAUGUCCAUGAAGGAGGUGGACGAGCAGAUGCUGGCCAUCCAGAGCAAGAACAGCAGCUACUUCGUGGAGUGGAUCCCCAACAACGUGAAGGUGGCCGUGUGUGACAUCCCGCCCCGCGGCCUCAAGAUGUCCUCCACCUUCAUCGGGAACAGCACGGCCAUCCAGGAGCUGUUCAAGCGCAUCUCCGAGCAGUUCACGGCCAUGUUCCGGCGCAAGGCCUUCCUGCACUGGUACACGGGCGAGGGCAUGGACGAGAUGGAGUUCACCGAGGCCGAGAGCAACAUGAACGACCUGGUGUCCGAGUACCAGCAGUACCAGGACGCCACGGCCGAGGAAGAGGGCGAGAUGUACGAAGACGACGAGGAGGAGUCGGAGGCCCAGGGCCCCAAGUGAAGCUGCUCGCAGCUGGAGUGAGAGGCAGGUGGCGGCCGGGGCCGAAGCCAGCAGUGUCUAAACCCCCGGAGCCAUCUUGCUGCCGACACCCUGCUUUCCCCUCGCCCUAGGGCUCCCUUGCCGCCCUCCUGCAGUAUUUAUGGCCUCGUCCUCCCCACCUAGGCCACGUGUGAGCUGCUCCUGUCUCUGUCUUAUUGCAGCUCCAGGCCUGACGUUUUACGGUUUUGUUUUUUACUGGUUUGUGUUUAUAUUUUCGGGGAUACUUAAUAAAUCUAUUGCUGUCAGAUACCCUU